CUGACUAGUCGUCGCCGUCUUCGCGGCUGCUAUGACCAGCGGGCGAGGCGCCCUUCGCAGCUCCGCGCAACGCUAGUCGCGGCCGUGCGCCCGCCGUAGCCGUCUGCGUCCCAGCGCGGCCGCUCCCGCGGCCCCCUCGGCUUUGCCAGCGCCGCCUGCGAGGCGGAGGCAGGAUGAAGAUGACUGUGGAUUUCGAGGAGUGUCUGAAGGACUCGCCCCGCUUCAGGGCAGCUUUGGAAGAAGUAGAAGGUGAUGUGGCAGAAUUGGAACUAAAACUUGAUAAGCUUGUGAAACUUUGUAUUGCAAUGAUUGAUACUGGAAAAGCCUUUUGUGUUGCAAAUAAACAGUUCAUGAAUGGGAUUCGAGACCUGGCUCAGUAUUCUAGUAAUGAUGCUGUCGUUGAGACAAGUUUGACCAAGUUUUCUGACAGUCUUCAAGAAAUGAUAAAUUUUCACACAAGACAAGGUCUCCCUUUGUCACUCAGGCUCGAGUGCAGGGGCAUGAUCAUAGCACUGCUCUGGGAAUCCUCCCACCUCAGGAUGAUCCUGUUUGACCAAACUCAGAGAUCAAUUAAGGCACAGCUUCAGAACUUUGUUAAAGAAGAUCUUAGAAAAUUCAAAGAUGCCAAGAAGCAAUUCGAAAAAGUCAGUGAAGAAAAAGAAAAUGCGUUAGUAAAAAAUGCCCAAGUACAAAGAAACAAACAACAUGAAGUUGAAGAAGCCACCAACAUUCUGACAGCAACAAGAAAAUGUUUCCGACACAUAGCCCUCGAUUAUGUGCUUCAGAUUAAUGUUCUUCAAUCAAAAAGGAGAUCAGAAAUCCUAAAAUCAAUGUUGUCAUUUAUGUAUGCCCAUUUGGCCUUCUUUCAUCAAGGAUAUGAUCUGUUUAGUGAACUUGGACCCUACAUGAAGGAUCUUGGUGCACAGUUGGAUCGACUGGUUGUGGAUGCAGCAAAGGAGAAAAGAGAAAUGGAGCAAAAACAUUCCACCAUUCAACAAAAGGAUUUCUCCAGUGAUGAUUCUAAGUUAGAAUAUAACGUAGAUGCUGCAAAUGGCAUAGUUAUGGAAGGAUAUCUGUUCAAACGAGCCAGCAAUGCCUUCAAAACUUGGAACAGGAAAAAGCCCGAUCACAUCAGGCGCUGGUUUUCAAUACAGAAUAAUCAGUUGGUUUACCAGAAAAAAUUUAAGGAUAAUCCGACUGUGGUAGUUGAAGACCUCAGGCUUUGCACAGUGAAACAUUGUGAAGACAUAGAGCGACGAUUCUGCUUUGAGGUGGUCUCGCCAACAAAAAGUUGCAUGCUCCAGGCAGAUUCCGAAAAGCUGCGCCAGGCAUGGAUUAAGGCUGUUCAGACCAGUAUUGCUACUGCUUAUAGAGAGAAGGGUGAUGAAUCAGAGAAGCUGGAUAAGAAAUCAUCUCCAUCCACAGGAAGCCUAGAUUCUGGAAAUGAGUCCAAAGAGAAAUUAUUGAAAGGAGAAAGUGCGCUUCAGCGGGUCCAGUGUAUCCCUGGCAAUGCCAGCUGUUGUGACUGUGGCCUGGCAGAUCCACGGUGGGCCAGCAUCAACCUGGGCAUCACCUUGUGUAUCGAGUGCUCCGGAAUUCACCGGAGCCUUGGGGUUCAUUUUUCAAAAGUACGAUCUUUAACUUUAGACACCUGGGAGCCAGAACUUUUAAAGCUUAUGUGUGAGUUGGGGAAUGAUGUUAUAAAUCGAGUUUAUGAAGCUAAUGUGGAAAAAAUGGGAAUAAAGAAACCCCAACCAGGACAAAGACAGGAGAAGGAGGCAUAUAUCAGAGCAAAAUAUGUGGAGAGGAAAUUUGUGGAUAAAUAUUCUAUAUCAUUAUCACCUCCUGAGCAGCAAAAAAAGUUUGUCUCUAAAAGUUCUGAAGAAAAGAGGCUGAGCAUUUCUAAAUUUGGGCCAGGGGACCAAGUCAGAGCAUCUGCCCAAAGUUCAGUGAUUGCUGUAAAUAGCGACGAGGCCAGGCGGGAGUCUCUGUUUUGUCCUGAUGAGCUAGAUUCACUCUUCUCCUACUUUGAUACUUCUUCAAAACUGCGUAGUAUCAGAAGUAAUGACAGUGGAAUUCAGCAGAGCUCUGAUGAUGGAAGAGAAUCUUUACCCUCCACGGUGUCAGCCAAUAGUUUAUAUGAGCCUGAAGGAGAAAGGCAAGAUUCUUCUAUGUUUCUUGACUCGAAACAUCUUAAUCCAGGACUUCAGCUUUAUAGGGCGUCAUAUGAAAAAAACCUUCCUAAAAUGGCUGAGGCUUUGGCUCAUGGUGCAGACGUGAACUGGGCCAAUUCAGAGGAAAACAAAGCGACACCACUUAUUCAGGCUGUAUUAGGGGGCUCUUUGGUGACGUGUGAGUUCCUCCUACAGAAUGGUGCUAAUGUCAACCAAAGAGAUGUCCAAGGGCGGGGACCAUUGCACCAUGCCACCGUCUUAGGGCACACAGGGCAGGUAUGUUUAUUCCUAAAACGAGGUGCCAAUCAACAUGCCACUGAUGAAGAAGGGAAAGACCCUUUGAGCAUAGCUGUGGAAGCAGCCAAUGCUGAUAUAGUCACCUUGUUACGUUUAGCAAGAAUGAAUGAAGAGAUGCGGGAAUCAGAAGGACUUUAUGGACAGCCAGGUCAAUAUUCUACUAAUAACCAUACUGAAAUGCAGUAUAAGAAAUGCAUUCAGGAAUUUAUCAGUUUACAACUGGAAGAUUCAUAGUUCUUUAGCAAACUAAUGUGAUACUAUAGAGUUUUUAUAACCCACUUGUAAAUUGUGAGUUGUUAGCUUUGUACUGUACUUAACUGAAUCCUUGGGUGGCUAAUCCCGGGCCUUUAAACAUUCGUAACUCUUCCUAUGACAGUACACAUUGACUUGCUCUAUUUCACUCUGGCUGCUGACUUCUUUAUUUGCUGUACGGAUGUCUUCCAUAUACAUUCCAGUGAAAUGAAUGGAAUGGUAAAAAUAUUCUUCAUAUACUUACAGCAGCAAAAUAGUUGUUUUCUUUUUGGAAUUCUUUUUAGCUGUCAAGUGAAUAUAACAAAAUUGUUUUCUUUUUGUUAUUCAGGGAAUUUCUAUAAAUUACGUUCAGGGAAAAAAAAAAUCACCAUGUGUCUGGCAUAUAAAAAGCCAGUAUGGAAAAUACCAAGAAAAAGUUUACUGAUGAGUUUUGUACUACAAUCUAAAAAUGAGUUGAAGAUUUAAAAUGAAAAUUCACCAGGUGGAGAAGUCCAUGAUGUGAGUGGAGCUAGUUUGAAAGGCUGAGGGCAAAGGUCUCAUUUUAUCUAAAGCUAAAGCUUUGCCUCCAGGCAGUUGUACAUUAUCUCUUAGAUAAGCGGAAGUAUUUAGAACAAUACUUUUUGCACCUGAUGGCAAAGUAGAUUUAUUCUACUUGAGAAAUUUCAAUUCAUGAUCACCUCAAGUUUCAUUUUGAGUAAUUUUCACCUUUGAAUCAAGAUGUCAAGGAAGAAGUAUCAGAUUCUUCUCUUUGAAGAACACGUUGAUUAGACGUUCUUCACAAAGAAGAGAGUAAUUAUUGGUUUUCUUGUUUCAUGAAUUUGAGUAUAUGAAUUACUCAUCUGUCUGUUUUAAAUUUAUAUACACAUUAGUAAAAAAUUUCAUGAAUUCGUGACUAAAAUACUUGAGAAUAUUCAGUUUGCAAUGAGUAGGUUUGGUUUUUUAAAAAUGAAUAUUGAUACAUUAUUUUUAAAGUGACCUGGUAAUAUCAUCUCUUCUUCCUGUUUAAAUACAUUUUGAAAUUUCUGUACUUCAGCCAUUUAUUUUAACGAGAUUAAUAUAUAGUUAAUGUGAGGCCGUUCUUUCCUCAGAGGACCGUAUUUACUACUGCUUAUUUUUGGCCUAAUUUAAUGUGGAACAAGUAAGAACGUUAAGAAUAGAGGCACUUCAGCUAGAUAUUUCUAAUCUAGGGUGUCCCACUUGAAUCCUAUGGAUCAUACAAUAGUAGGCGGCUCAUGAUGUUCCGAGAUGGAAGAGUGCUGAUGAAGGGUGAAGCUCUAGCGUUCAUUCUGGAUUUCACCCAUUUGUUUCAAACUUGAAUGUUAGAUUUUAAAUAGGUUAUAAUUUUAUAACAGAUAUUCUUAACUGAUAGUAUUACUAGGCCGUUUUUGAGGCCUUUGUGUUUAAGCACUUUAAAAUAAAAAUUGUUUAAAGAAUAUGACCUGAUAUUUGUAAGAGAAGAGUGAACCUCACGAUUUUAAGUUAAACAAUUAUUUUCCCCCUGACAUUUUUAACUUCAGUGUUUGGUUAGCUGCUCUUUCCUUACGGUGUCUGCUGAUGAAGUUCACCCAGCUGAUUAGCCAGGUGGUCAGUGGUCGACUCUUCUCUGGAGUUGGGAAGCUUGAAAGGAAAGGGCCUCUAAGUUCUUGCCACUUCUAGUUCCACCCAAAUUGUUUGGGUGUCUGCCACCAUCAUUUAGGAGCAUUCAAAUGUCUUCCACUGUCAUUUUUGAGUUUAUAUAUACAUAAACUUAAAAUGUAUAGAAAAGAUUUUACCAAUUUAAUUUAAUGAAAACUUGAAAAAAAAAGCCUCAUUUUAAAACAAGCUCUCUUACCAUUCUCACAUUUUAGUUUAGAGGUUAAAAAAUAGACCAGAAUUCUGGAAAUAGUAUAUCAGAAUAAAAUUGAGAUAUUUCUGAUUUAUUUGAGGAUCAUCUUGAGAAGGGUUAGAUUUUUAACUCAUUCAGAGGGCCUAAUAUUUAAAGCAGGAUGAUUUUAUGCUUAGACAGGGGACAUGGUGAAAUGGCAUAGCAAUUGCUCUUCGGUUUCUGUUCUUUUUCUUUAUGAGACAGGUAUGUUUGGCUCAGGCAGCGGCUGUUUGUUUUUCCUCUGCUUAUCACUGUACAUUUUUCUAUCAAAUGCUUUGGUUGCUUGUUUUAUUGAGAUCCUUUUUUGGUUUUCUUAGCAAUAGAAUGAAAACCUCAGAACUCUGGGUAAAUUAAAUGCAGGUAUUUUUAAUCUUUUGAUAAUGAAGAGCUCUUAUCCUUUAAAAGAUUCAGAUGUAAUCUUUGGCAAUCACUGAUUUAUUUCUAGGAAACCCCACUUGUGAACUUUCUAUCUGUACAACCCUAGGGACCUGGGACUCCCUGUUUCUUGCGUGGGGUGAUUGAGAGCACACGUUUUCUUCAAAAGAAGGUGUGUCUCUCUUUGGCAGUCCCAGUAGCCCUUAGGAGACAUGGGUGGGUGAGGGAAACAGCACACUCUUCUCUCAGUUGUUGGAAACCGGUUUGGUGGUUCCCACAGUCUCUGGCUCUGUGACUCUUCUUGAUCGUUGGCAGGCUCUCAGCCAGUUGAGAAUCAUCACUGCUUUAGGGACCCGCUACUGGUUAUGUGAGUAUGUAGCAAGCACAAGUUGGGAAUCGCUGAUCUAAGUAAUUAUGAAAGUAAGCUGUUACCCACCCAGAAGGGGUAAGGUCGUGCAUAGGAUGACCUGGGGUGGGUCUCAUGUGCUGCCGUCCCUGUGAGGUGAGGGGAGUACAUUUCAAGAGCAAAAUUAGCAAACUCUUGAAUCAUCAUAACUGCUGUUGUGGUAGAUAUUCUGAAUACCAAAAAUUAAAAGUGAAUUUAAACUGUCAGUGGAAACACAGCAGUCUGCAUUUUAAAAACUUAGAGCUGUCCAGGCACAUAGAAAAGUUAACUGUCUGAGGGGAAAUAGAAUGUGGUUAAGUUUAAAGAAUAUGCUUAGUAUUAUAAAUGUUGAGUGAUGAGUUGUUUACCAUUUAUAAUAAACUGUUAAAUGUAUUUCUGGGAACAUUCCAUGGCAGCAUAUUCUGGGUUGUUGUUUAUGUGUUCCAAUGUAGACAAAUUAUAUUUGCCUUGGGAAAAAUUCUAAGUAAUCAAAAUUAUAUUUAAAUAUUAAAAAAUCACAUUGAAGUUCAAUUUGUGUUAGCUGUAUUAAAUAUCUUGGUCACUAUUGUUCUUGUAACAUUUGCUUUUGACAACACAUUUUGAGAUCUAAGAAAGGUAGUACAUUAACAGUGCAUUAAUUAAUGUUUUGUUAGAAACUAAAUGUUAACAAAAAGUUUUGUGUGUAUGUGAAGGUGGCAACUUCCUUUUGUAUUAUAUUAACACUUUUUAAAUGUAUUCAGUCAGUGAAACCAAUGAUUAUUAUAGCACCAACACUUUCAUUCAAGGAAGCAUUUGAGUCUUAUAAUUUGUUUUGCAUGGUACAAUGGUUCUACUAAAAUAUACUUGUGUAAUAGGUACUAGAUGAUUUAAAAACAAAACCGGAGAAACCAUUUAAAAAGUUCCAUAGCUUGUUAUACAAAAUAUGCAUUGCUAAUAGUAGAAGCCAUAUAUUGCCAUUGUACUGUUGUAAUACUUAACAGUGCUCAUCUGGUGCUACCUGUAGACUAUUUGGUAUUAACGUCUGCUAGACCCUUCUUCCUAUUUCUUCUUGAAUGUAUAAUGUGUGCCUUUUAAGUUACUUCUAGUGUUGAAUGGUAAAAUCUUUGUGGUAUUUUUGUAUUAUACUCUGCACUUUACACUUUCUUGGAAAGGAAAAUUCCAGACUAUCCAGUUUAAAUAGUCUUUUAAAAAUAUUUAUAAUGUUUACAAUAAAUAUUUUACAUAUUUUAAUUCAACAUCUGCAAAUUAGAAAAAAUAUUUUAUAUGGUUUGUUGCUAUUUAAUGUUGCUCUAUUUAUUUUCUAUCUUUUAGAAUGGUUAAAAUGAGAAUAGCAAUGUUUGUCUUUUGAUGUGGAAGUGAACUUUUACAAAACCAUGGGUAUAAUUGGAUUGUCUUACCAGCUGUUCCAACGUAUCAACCUUUUAUUUUAGUCAUGUCAAUAUGAGUUAGAUGUUACUCUCAGCCACCUGUUAAUAAUCUCUUCUUACUGUUUUUUUCUUUUUAAAGUAGACUGAUGAGGUUUAAUUGAUUGAUUCAGGUCGGGAAUAAAUUUCCAGGGCUAAAUGAAAACUAUAUAGAGAUGUUAAUAGUUGCUUUUUACCUAGACUAAAUACAAAAAGUGACUAGAAAGUAUUAGAUUUUUUUUCCUUUUUUUUCUUUUUUUGAGGCGGAGUCUCGCUCUGUUGCCCAGGCUGGAGUGCAGUGGCGCGAUCUUGGCUCACUGCAAGCUCUGCCUCCCGGGUUCACACCAUUCUCAUGCCUUGGCCUCCCGAGUAGCUGGGACUACAGGCGCCCACCACCACGCCCGGCUAAUUUUUUGUAUUUUUAAUAGAGACGGGGUUUCACCGUGUUAGCCAGGAUGGUCUCCAUCUCCUGACCUCGUGAUCCGCCCGUCUCGGCCUCUCAAAGUGCUGGGAUUAGAGGCGUGAGCCACCCGGCCGGGCCAAAAGUAUUAACAUUUUUUUAAUUCAAAAUCUUGGCUUAUGCUGUUAGACCUUUUUACUAGAUCUUUACUCCUAUCCUCAACUUUUUUCUAAUUCUCUAGCUUUUGGUAUGACAUCUCUUGCUUCAAAAAUCUCACUUUUUAAAAACUGACAAAACUUACUGCACUAUUAACAACAUCUGUAGCAAUGAGUGUGUUAUAAGGUGGAUGCAAGGUAUCUUAUAGGAGAUAAUUUUAAAAUGUUACAAUAAUAAUCAAAAACAGUAUUUUAUGGUUGAAAUCUUGAGAACAGAAUUAUGCCAAGCAUUUGUAUAAGGCUAAUGUUUAGCAGGAAGCAUUCAUGAUCAACGAUUUAUCUUGAAAAUAAGAUUCCUUCGUCUGAGGGAUUGAUCUGUAUGUGUGUGUAUAUUUAGUUUCUCAUGACAAGAAAAAUGGUAUUCAGUCAGCUAUAAUAUCAGUAUCUAUAAUCUAUUUCUCGGUAAACAUAUUUGUACAUAUACACGUUUAUUUUUCUAAUUUAACAGAUGUCCUUGGUAUUUAUUUGCAUUUUGUCAUAGCAUUCUUGCUCAUAUGACCUGCAGUAAAACAAAAACAAACCCAACUUUUAAAUGCAAAACUGAUUUUAAAGCCAUUUUCUUUUUUUUAUUUUUUAUUGAAACAGAGUCUCGCUCUGUUGCCCAGGCUGGAGUGCAGUGGUGCGAUCUCAGCUCACUGCAACCUCCACCUCCCGGGUUCAAGCGAUUCUCCUGCCUCAGCCUCCCGAGUAGCUGGGAUUACAGGUGCCCACCACCACGCCUGGUUACUUUUUGUAUUUUUAGUAGAGACAGGGUUUCAUCAUGUUGGCCGGGCGGUCUCAAACUCCUGACCUCAGGUGAUCUGCCCGCCUCAGCCUCCCAAAGUGCUGGGGUUACAGGCAUGAGCCACCACACCUGGCCUUAAAGCCAUUUUCUAGGAUUUUGUUGUUAAUUUUUGUAGAGAUGUAGUCUCGCUAUGUUGCCCAGACUGGUCUUGAACUCCUGGCCUCAACCAAUUCUCCCCCCAACCCCCCCACCCAGCUUCCCAAAGUGUUGGGGUUAUAGGCGUGAGGCACUGCACCCAGCUAGAUUUUUAUUUUAUGAGUUUAGGAAGCAGUGGAUUAGGUGCAUUAGUUUUAAUUACGCAUUAAAGUUUGAGUAAAAAAUUACUUUUUCAAAUUGCUUUUAAUUAAAAGAUAGUAUUAUUUUUCCCUAUCUGAUUAUCAGUUUGUCUUGAUUAUCAGUUUGUCUUGUUAAUAACUUGCAUCCAUCCAAAACAUUAGUAUUUGGUUUUAGUCAUUUCUUUUGGCCUUUAUCAAGGGAAAUAUUUAUUUAAAGAAGGUCUCAUUUACUCCACCUCAUUUAGAAUGACUUUUCCCCCCCGUGUGUUAAUAAACGUAUUUCUUUACAUUGCUUUAAAA